ACACACACGCGCCCUCACCCGCCACCGCCGCCGCGGCCGCCGCCGCACCCGGACAGCGAGCGGCUGAGGCCGCCAGGGCCCAAAGGACAGCGGCCCAGACAGGGGCUGGCGGCCCGGCCGGCCCCGGCUCACCGACUCGGGCAGCAUCCACCUGCCCCAGCCAACACCCUUCUCUCGCCCCAGGUCCUUUCUCAGCCUCCAGCUGGGCUGUCCCCAAGCUGAGCUGAGGCUCUUCUCCUCCGAUCCCCACCUCUGCCCGGACAUCCACCAUGGGGACAGCCACCAGGAGGAAGCCACACCUGCUGCUGGUAGCUGCUGUGGCCCUUGUCUCCUCUUCAGGUGAAGAUACUGAGGCUCAGAAGAGUUCUAUAACUUUCCCAAGGUCCCACAGCUAGUAGAGGGCCAGCCUAGUCCCCAGGCCCAGGCCUCGUUGGUCCACACUGCCCCAGUAAGGGUAUUAGGCUCCAGGGACACACAUCCUCUCUGCAUGUUUGUGGCUGGCGACGUCUCAUGCACCUCACACCCCACAGAUCAGUUCUUCUCUUGGAGUUCAGCCCUGGGAUCCCAAACCACCUUCGGGCCUGUCUUUGAAGACCAGCCCCUCAGUGUGCUAUUCCCAGAGGAGUCCACGGAGGAGCAGGUGUUGCUGGCAUGCCGCGCCCGGGCCAGCCCUCCAGCCACCUAUCGGUGGAAGAUGAAUGGUACCGAGAUGAAGCUGGAGCCAGGUUCCCGUCACCAGCUGGUGGGGGGCAACCUGGUCAUCAUGAACCCCACCAAGGCACAGGAUGCCGGGGUCUACCAGUGCCUGGCCUCCAACCCAGUGGGCACCGUUGUCAGCAGGGAGGCCAUCCUCCGCUUCGGCUUUCUGCAGGAAUUCUCCAAGGAGGAGCGAGACCCAGUGAAAGCUCAUGAAGGCUGGGGGGUGAUGUUGCCCUGUAACCCACCUGCCCACUACCCAGGCUUGUCCUACCGCUGGCUCCUCAACGAGUUCCCCAACUUCAUCCCGACGGACGGGCGUCACUUCGUGUCCCAGACCACAGGGAACCUGUACAUUGCCCGAACCAAUGCCUCAGACCUGGGCAACUACUCCUGUUUGGCCACCAGCCACAUGGACUUCUCCACCAAGAGCGUCUUCAGCAAGUUUGCUCAGCUCAACCUGGCUGCUGAAGAUACCCGGCUCUUUGCACCCAGCAUCAAGGCCCGGUUCCCAGCAGAGACCUAUGCACUGGUGGGGCAGCAGGUCACCCUGGAGUGCUUCGCCUUUGGGAACCCUGUCCCCCGGAUCAAGUGGCGCAAAGUGGACGGCUCCCUGUCCCCGCAGUGGACCACAGCUGAGCCCACCCUGCAGAUCCCCAGCGUCAGCUUUGAGGAUGAGGGCACCUACGAGUGUGAGGCGGAGAACUCCAAGGGCCGAGACACCGUGCAGGGCCGCAUCAUCGUGCAGGCUCAGCCUGAGUGGCUAAAAGUGAUCUCGGACACAGAGGCUGACAUUGGCUCCAACCUGCGUUGGGGCUGUGCAGCCGCCGGCAAGCCCCGGCCUACAGUGCGCUGGCUGCGGAACGGGGAGCCUCUGGCCUCCCAGAACCGGGUGGAGGUGUUGGCUGGGGACCUGCGGUUCUCCAAGCUGAGCCUGGAAGACUCGGGCAUGUACCAGUGUGUGGCAGAGAAUAAGCACGGUACCAUCUACGCCAGCGCCGAGCUAGCCGUGCAAGCACUCGCCCCUGACUUCAGGCUGAAUCCCGUGAGGCGUCUGAUCCCCGCGGCCCGCGGGGGAGAGAUCCUUAUCCCCUGCCAGCCCCGGGCAGCUCCAAAGGCCGUGGUGCUCUGGAGCAAAGGCACGGAGAUUUUGGUCAACAGCAGCAGAGUGACUGUAACUCCAGAUGGCACCUUGAUCAUAAGAAACAUCAGCCGGUCAGAUGAAGGCAAAUACACCUGCUUUGCUGAGAACUUCAUGGGCAAAGCCAACAGCACUGGAAUCCUAUCUGUGCGAGAUGCAACCAAAAUCACUCUAGCCCCCUCAAGUGCCGACAUCAACUUGGGUGACAACCUGACCCUACAGUGCCAUGCCUCCCACGACCCCACCAUGGACCUCACCUUCACCUGGACCCUGGACGACUUCCCCAUCGACUUUGAUAAGCCUGGAGGGCACUACCGGAGAACUAAUGUGAAGGAGACCAUUGGGGAUCUGACCAUCCUGAACGCCCAGCUGCGCCAUGGGGGGAAGUACACGUGCAUGGCCCAGACGGUGGUGGACAGCGCGUCCAAGGAGGCCACAGUCCUGGUCCGAGGUCCGCCAGGUCCCCCAGGAGGUGUGGUGGUGAGGGACAUUGGCGACACCACCAUCCAGCUCAGCUGGAGCCGUGGCUUCGACAACCACAGCCCCAUCGCUAAGUACACCCUGCAAGCUCGCACUCCACCUGCAGGGAAGUGGAAGCAGGUUCGGACCAAUCCUGCAAACAUCGAGGGCAAUGCCGAGACUGCACAGGUGCUGGGCCUCACCCCCUGGAUGGACUAUGAGUUCCGGGUCAUAGCCAGCAACAUUCUGGGCACUGGGGAGCCUAGUGGGCCCUCCAGCAAAAUCCGGACCAGGGAAGCAGCCCCCUCGGUGGCACCCUCAGGACUCAGCGGAGGAGGUGGAGCCCCCGGAGAGCUCAUCGUCAACUGGACGCCCAUGUCACGGGAGUACCAGAACGGAGACGGCUUCGGCUACCUGCUGUCCUUCCGCAGGCAGGGCAGCACUCACUGGCAGACCGCCCGGGUGCCUGGCGCCGAUGCCCAGUACUUUGUCUACAGCAACGAGAGCGUCCGGCCCUACACGCCCUUUGAGGUCAAGAUCCGCAGCUACAACCGCCGCGGGGAUGGGCCCGAGAGCCUCACUGCACUCGUGUACUCAGCUGAGGAAGAGCCCAGGGUGGCCCCUACCAAGGUGUGGGCCAAAGGGGUCUCAUCCUCAGAGAUGAACGUGACCUGGGAACCCGUGCAGCAGGACAUGAAUGGUAUCCUCCUGGGGUAUGAGAUCCGCUACUGGAAAGCUGGGGACAAAGAAGCAGCUGCGGACCGAGUGAGGACAGCAGGGCUGGACACCAGUGCCCGAGUCAGCGGCCUGCAUCCCAACACCAAGUACCAUGUGACCGUGAGGGCCUACAACCGGGCUGGCACUGGGCCUGCCAGCCCUUCUGCCAACGCCACGACCAUGAAGCCCCCUCCGCGGCGACCUCCUGGCAACAUCUCCUGGACUUUCUCAAGCUCUAGUCUUAGCAUUAAGUGGGACCCUGUGGUCCCUUUCCGAAAUGAGUCUGCAGUCACCGGCUAUAAGAUGCUGUACCAGAAUGACUUACACCUGACUCCCACGCUCCACCUCACCGGCAAGAACUGGAUAGAAAUCCCAGUGCCUGAAGACAUUGGCCAUGCCCUGGUACAAAUUCGGACCACAGGGCCCGGAGGGGAUGGGAUCCCUGCAGAAGUCCACAUCGUGAGGAAUGGAGGUGCUGCUCCUCCCCUACCCUUAUCCCCUCGAGAGAUUCAGGAUCCACCCAGAUACCUGAGAGGAUCAUUCCCACCCAGGCCAACUCCAAUCUCUACCCGCAAAGGAAAGUGGAAGGCAGGCAGGAACCAAGUGCAAAGUAGUCUUAGAACUGCCUCGCCGCCACCUUUCUACCCAGCCCCCAGAACAUCCCCGAGGGCCAGGGAAGGGCGCAGGGUGCAGGGGGAGGCUGAGGACCAACCAGCAAUAGCAAACGGCCUACAAAGCACCGUAGGAGUCGGACUGAGAAGACCACCCAGCCGUCCGCUCCCAGGCCUGCAGCUGGCCCUGCACAAGCAUGAUGGUGGAGAACAUGGCAGUCCGCCCAGCACCACACCCUGGCACCGUCAUUUCCCACUCCGUGGCGAUGCUGAUCCUCAUAGGCUCCCUGGAGCUCUGAUCCUGGAACCCCUCCCUCUGCGCCGCAGCUGGACGCCACCUCCGACGGACACAGCCAGCCCCUUCCUGCUGCCAAGGUGGCCUGACACUGUGCCAGAGAGUGGCUGGUUUUAAAUACCUACUUUAAACAGUGCCCUUUUUGUAGGAGGUAGGAUAUUUUAUAUUCUGCCGCAGGAUAGAACCCACGCAAGGAUUUUCUUUAAAUUGAGAGGCACCAGGCAGUAACUUCCAUGAUGACACUGACGCCUAUACCUGAGCUCUAGGCUGCCUGGAGGGAAGGAACAGGCCCAUGGGAAGAAGGGGGUUUUAAAAACAUGUCUUCAACUCAGCAGAGAUGGCCCUCUGGGACCCUAUACGGACUCCGCCACUUGAGAGCAGUCCUAGGCCCGGCAGGAACACCAGACAUGAACAGGUUGAAGAACUGGAGCGAAGUGCACACCUCACCAUCCUUCAGUCUAAGGAAGAAGGGCAAGCCCUGGGACCAAGAGCUCUCCCGCCUUCUCCCUCGAGCAGCAGCAAGGACCCUGACGCUGUCCCCGAUAACUCCCUAGGGGCUCCUGCCUGCCCAAGCGGCUGAGAACCAGCGCCCCGAUGCCUGAGGCUGGGAGCCUGAGCCCCUUCAGCUUUGAGGGGGGUGAUACUCCAGGCUGUUUGGGGUGGGAGCCAAAAAGAGUUGAGAGGCCAGGGCCCUUGGUGGAAAGGGGCACCAGCCUUGGUCUGAGAUAGUCACAACCCAGGUGACGAUGCCCUCUCAGCCAACACUGCCAACCUGACCCUGUCAUCCCGAUUGACAGCGCCACUUCAGGUGGCUGGGUGACUAAAGGGCUUGUCUUGGUGGGGUCUCCCACCCCUCCAAGACCCAUUCUGCACAGUCCCUCCAGGGUUUGGGCAGGAGAUGGCCAAUCAUGCGCCCACCUCUCCAGUGCUGCCUGCAGUCAGCUCGGCCUCCCCGACCUGCAGCCCCAGACUCUGCUCUCCCAGCACUGACUCACUCCUGCCUGGGAGGGGAAUGCAGCAUUCAUGCUGUGUGUCCUGGUAUUGGGAGGUUUCUGGGAAGGGCAGAGGAUAAAUGUGGCCCUGCCUGCUCCCAGGUAUACCUAGGACCACCUGGCCAGAUCCGCUCCCAGACGGCCUUGGACUGCUUGCAUUUCCCCGGAGAAAAAGGGGUUAAUAAAUGGGCCAUCCUUUCCUGAGCUCUGGGUAUACUACCAGUCACAGAACGUCAGAGCUGGAAGAAGCCUUAGAGCUCAACUUCUUCAAGCCCCUCACUUUACAGAUGAGGAAAUGGAGGUGGUCCAGAGAGGGUCUGGGAUUCCCAAGGUCACACAGCCCAGAAGAGAUGGGGCUGGGUUAAGAACUCGAGUCUUCCACCUUUCUGUUCAAGGCUGUUUGUCUACCCAGAGGAAGGAGGCACUGCUGAAUGGCUAUGGCCUGGCUAAGAAGGUGAUUAGUCAGUAGGGUGUGAAAAUUCUACUUCAAGGGGUUCGGAUUGGUGAUCAUGGGGAUUGGCAUGGCUGGGUUCCCGUCCAAGGUGUGGGCAGAGCUUCUACCAAACUUCAACAUGGAGGGCUGACUUGAAGCUCCCUGUCCCCCUCACUCUUGCCCCAAGAAAAGAGGCCAAAGCAAGAGCAGAUUCCCUAGGCAAGAGCAGCAGCACAACUAGGAAACCCCAAAGCCCAUGCUCCGACAGGUGGCCCUUCACAGGGGGCAGCGGGACAGGCAUCUUGAAGGGCAUAUGUCCUCGGAAGCUCCGAGCCUGUUUUCUGUAGUUUAUAGUUAGAGCUCUAUUUUGUUAUGGUUUUUUAAACUUUUAAGUCCUGCUCUAUUUUCCUGGGCAGGUUUAUGUUGAUGUUUACCCACUACAAUUUUUUAAAAAUAUAAGCUCACAUGCCUUUUCCCUGCCACAGCCAAACCCCCACUGCACCCUACCCACCCACCCCUAGCCCAGGUCAGCUUUCCUGGAGCUGGCUAAUGAAAGCCUCCUCACCUCUUCCCAACCCUUACAAGCAAGGGUGCUAGGGGCUCAGCUAUACGACCAUUCUCCCUGACAGGGAGUCCAAACUUGGCCUAGCAUCCCUCCUGGCCCCCCUCUGGCCACGACUUGGCCUGUGCCUGGUUCUCUAUCAGAAAGGGGAUGCUGAACAAAACCUCCUUCCAAGUUUUAUCCAAUUCGUUCCUCAUUGCCUCGGGCUGCGUCAGGGGAAGCAGGGGACAGGUGUCCAGUUGCUGGGCCGAGGGAGGAGCUGGUUUGGCAUAGGACCUAACCAGUGAAGCUAGAGGCUACAGCCACUAAACUUGCUUCAGGCCAACGAUAGUUACUCACAAGUAAGUACCUUAAUGCUAAUGAGGUCCACUAAAAAGGGGAGGAAGGCAGACCUCCUGGGAGACCCACGAAGGGUUUUUAGCCAGGGAAAACUGAGCCCCAGGAAAACCUAACCACUGGGCAGGCAGAAUUUGUUUGAGGGAUAGAACGACAACAAAAUAAAUGUUCCUGCAGCCUGAGAUUUCAGGUAGAGUACUGACUAAGGUUUAAUAAGACAAUAGGUGACCUGAGGACAUGCAAGCUUGUAAAAUGCAACAGCCUCCUGCUAGAGUGACUUGUACAUGAGCUUGCUUGCAGAAGACUAGAUUAGAUGUUUCUCAGGAUCCCCUCCUGCGCAGGGGUUCUCUGAUUUUCGUGUUCUCUGCCCAGAUGGGCUGGGGGAGUUGAGAGUGUGCUUAUUUUCACUGCGAUCAUGAGACCACAGUUCUGGGUUAUCUCCUCUCAUACAUCAAGCCCCAGAGGAGGCGGCAAGAGGAACAGCCACAAACAAGUACUUUACCCCACAGCUUAGUGGCCAGUAAACACCCUGGGGACUAGGAAAAGGAACCAACUGUAGGCACCUCUCCAGGGCCUAGGGAGACAAGUGUCCUCUCUUCUGCAUACAUUUGGGCUCCCCUUACAGAGCCCUUUGCCCUGGCUCUCUGGUCCUUGUUGCUCUAACAGUCCAGAUGUACACCCAGCCUCAGGGGGAAGGCAGCUCUCUCCAGACAGAGUCUCAGGGCCCAGCAAGGUCAGGUUAUCUGCUUUCAUUCAGGGCAACAAAUGAUACAAAUGGUGCCAGGGAGUGGCAAGGCCAUGGGGGUAGGUGGGGGUGUCUUUUUCUUUUCAUAAAGUAACAACAGACGAGACUGAGGUUAAACAUCAGAAAAAAACCUCUGGAAUGACCUUCCUCAUUCCAGGAGGCCCUGGAAUAAGGAAGAGGCUUCUUUCUGAGGGAGCUUUGAGGAAUUUUGACAGCUGUUGACAUGGGAUUUGGGAAAGGUGAAGCUGUGACUGGAGGGGCAGGAGAUGGUCCAAGUGUCCAUCCAGAGAUGAGACUCUUAGAAUCAAAGUGUUCAGCCCAGGAAGUCUUGGAGAUCCCACCUUCUGUGGCCCUGCACCUUAUGGGAAGCCAUUAAGGGGGCUCAUCUAGGAAUUCUGGUUACAGCCCAGUGCUCAUCCCAGCGUAUGCUGCCUCUUUAGGGCAGCCCCAAGGGCCAGCCAGCCUGUACUCUGGGCAAGAGCCCAAAAUGGCUAGGAAUGUUUGACUCCCUUAAUCUCUUCCCCAGCUACAGAGGAAUCUUUUCUCUGCCUGGUCUCAGAAUGGGACUGCCAACUGGCUCAUUGGUGGGAGACACAGUAUCCUCAAACCUGUGGCCACUGGCAUGACAGUGGUGCUCUGUCUCCCUGGGUGACACCCACCCUAGGCUUCCUCCUGGAUGUGAUGGGGAUUGCCAGAGAGGCUCUUAGCAUAAAAGGCAUUAGGUGGGCAUUUUUCUGUGUGCCCCCAAAAAGCUCCAUGGAAACAGGCACCUGGUAGCUGCGGAACACCCGUGGACUUGUGUAUAUGGUCAUAGGCUUUGGGAAGACAGGACGUAAAGGAAAAUGAGAGAAACAAAAUGGGUCAGAUAGCUUUGGCCACAGCCCCAGGCAGCCUUUGGGGCCUAUGACACUUAGUGCCCUUAGAUGGGAUACAUCUUGCCUCGGCCCCAAGACUCCUCCAACUUACCCGUCCCAUCCAGGGCCUGCACAGCUUAGAGAGGCUCACAGCUUGGCAAAUGCUAGGGCUUCAUCAGACCACUGACUUGACUCAGUGUUUGUUAAAAUGGAACCACUCCCGUUGGCCUACUGUUUCUCUCCUGUACUUCUUGUAAUGAUAGUUAUUUAUUGACUCUGGUAGCAGGCAGUUCUUAAAUAAAGAUGGUUUCUCAACCUGUUGGGGAAGCUGGCACGAGCUGUGGGUGUUAUCAUCAGGCUAAAGCAUACCUCCUUGUCCUGUUCUUCACUCCAGAGGCUUUUAUCCAAGAAUUUCUUUACCCCCCACACAGUGAAAUAUAAGUAAGUUACAACAUACAGUCUAUAUUGCUUCAUCCAGUCCCAGGAGGAGGGAAAAAUUAGGCCAAGAUCUUAAGGCAGGUCCAAGCAGAGCACAGGCAGGCAUUUGGCUAGAAUCAGUUGGCUUUACCUAAUACAGUGGCAGUAAACAAUGCUUAUGUGAUGGUA